GGGGUGCCCAGGGUACCCCCAUGCCAGCCUCUUUGUCCGGACACAGGCAUGGCUGGGGGACCAGGGAUGGUCCAGCUCUGUGCUGGCCGCCGGCAGGGAGGGAGCCUGGAGCCCGUGGGAGCCCGAGGGCCUGGCGGGAGGCGGCAGGAAGUGUGUGCUGAGCCAGGGCAGGGAGGAGGAAUGUGAGCUAUGAACGCCGCCCGAGCUCCUCGGCUCUCUGGGCCCCCCUUCCCCACGAGCCCAUGUGCUGCCAGCAGCCCACCCUGGCCCCUCCAUUGCAGCCCCUCCACCUGAGGUUUUAGUGCUGUGCCUGGCGCCACUGGGACCCUGCUGACAAUGAAGGGGUUUAGGUUUGAUAGGCAGAACUUCUUGCCUUGUAGAGUGAAAGACGGCUGCUUCUGGACAGAGGCAGAGGGGUGGCCAGAAUGACCCUGAGAACACUGAGGGGUCCUUGGCCUGGCCUCAGGGCCCCAGACACCCACCAGAUCCUGCUUCCUGUCUGGUGCCCUGAGAAACCCUGCCCCGCAGGCCGCUGUGCAGGCGUGGGAAGGGCUGCCGGGCCAGCACUGUGGGGCUGGCCGCAUGUGUGGGCUGCUGUGCGUGUUUGCAGGUGUGUGUGGACGUCUUGUGUCUGUGGCUGUGUGAUGUGUCUUUGCGGACUGGGCCCAUAUCACGCUCCCACCUCCUCCACUGAAUUGGGCUCCUGUCCCCACGCCUUCCCUGCGUCCCAGGCCAGCCUGGGGGCCGUGCUCCACCUCCCCUCCCGAACUGGACUCCUGUCCCCACGCCUUCCCUCCGUCCCAGGCCAGCCUGGGGGCCGUGCUCCACCUCCCCUCCCGAACUGGACUCCUGUCCCCACGCCUUCCCUCCGUCCCAGGCCAGCCUGGGGGCCGUGCUCCACCUCCCCUCCCGAACUGGACUCCUGUCCCCACGCCUUCCCUCCGUCCCAGGCCAGCCUGGGGGCCGUGCUCCACCUCCCCUCCCGAACUGGGCUCCUGUCCCCACGCCUUCCCUCCGUCCCAGGCCAGCCUGGGGGCCGUGCUCCACCUCCCCUCCCGAACUGGACUCCUGUCCCCACGCCUUCCCUCCGUCCCAGGCCAGCCUGGGGGCCGUGCUCCACCUCCCCUCCCGAACUGGGCUCCUGUCCCCACGCCUUCCCUCCGUCCCAGGCCAGCCUGGGGGCUGUGCUCCACUUCCCCUCCCGAACUGGACUCCUGUCCCCACGCCUUCCCUGCGUCCCAGGCCAGCCUGGGGGCCGUGCUGUGACUGCAUCCCUGAGGGGCACUUUGGUGGGCAGGUGUCAGGGUCAGCCUUGAAGCCCCACGCCUGUGCCACCAGGUGUGUCUGGGGGAGGAGUGAGUCUAUGUGGUGGGGCCCUGGAGAUUUUGGGGGUCUUGCACCCUCUAAUUCAGCCCAUGUGGCCCAGCUGAGCCCCUGUGGGGCCAGGGAGCCACAGGCUUGUCCCUGGAGUUUCUGGUGUGACGGGCUGGGUGGUGGCCAUGCAGAGAGGGUUCAGAGGGUGGGCAGGAGGCUUCAGAUGAGGCAUCUGGCAGGCUGGACAGGAGAAGGGUGUUCCAGACCAAGGGCAGGUCCUGAGCCCAGGGGACAGAGCACUAGCUGUGUGGAGAAGGACCCCCUUGCUCCCUUGGCGGGGCGGUCCCCCCCGCUGACAUGGCCGUUUCUGGUCCAUUGGGGUUUGGAGCGAGCUUGAAGGUGGGUGGCUGGAGGGGUUGGGGGUGUCUGAGGCCUGGAGACCUGCCCUCCUGAGGUCUGAGCGCCCCCUUGCCAUGCCGCCCCAGCCCUGGCCUGGCCUGGCCUGUGGUCCCUCAGGGACACACAGGGAGGUAGGAGGUGAGGGAAGGGCCCUGGCAGCCCCCAGCCCGCCUGCACAGUCUCCCCUGCGCACGCCCUCAAGCUUGGCGCUCCCUGGAAACCUGAGCUGCCUCCUGCCUGCUCCGGCCACCGCCAUGUUUAACUGAGCACGGGCAGCCGCUGGCCACCGCCGCCGCACCCUGGCCCACCCCCUGGCUGGGAGGUGGUCAUUGGGCCUGGCCUUGCCUGCAUGGUCCCCUGGCCCAGAGCCCUACCGCAGGAUGCCAGAGGAUGUCAGUGGGCCCCUGAGGGAGCUGCGCCCUCGGCUCUGCCACCUGCGAAAGGGACCUCAGGGCUAUGGGUUCAACCUGCAUAGUGACAAGUCCCGGCCCGGCCAGUACAUCCGCUCUGUGGACCCGGGCUCACCUGCCGCCCGCUCUGGCCUCCGCGCCCAGGACCGGCUCAUUGAGGUGAACGGGCAGAAUGUGGAGGGACUGCGCCAUGCUGAGGUGGUGGCCAGCAUCAAGGCACGGGAGGACGAGGCCCGGCUGCUGGUCGUGGACCCCGAGACAGAUGAACACUUCAAGCGGCUUCGGGUCACACCCACCGAGGAGCACGUGGAAGGUCCUCUGCCGUCACCCGUCACCAAUGGAACCAGCCCUGCCCAGCUCAAUGGUGGCUCUGCGUGCUCGUCCCGAAGUGACCUGCCUGGUUCCGACAAGGACACUGAGGAUGGCAGUGCCUGGAAGCAAGAUCCCUUCCAGGAGAGCGGCCUCCACCUGAGCCCCACGGCGGCCGAGGCCAAGGAGAAGGCUCGAGCCAUGCGAGUCAACAAGCGCGCGCCACAGAUGGACUGGAACAGGAAGCGUGAAAUCUUCAGCAACUUCUGAGCCCCUUCCUGCCUGUCUCGGGACCCUGGGACCCCUCCCGCACGGACCUUGGGCCUCAGCCUGCCCCGAGCUCCCCCAGCCUCAGUGGACUGGAGGGUGGUCCUGCCAUUGCCCAGAAAUCAGCCCCAGCCCCGGUGAGCCCCCAUCCUGCCCCUGCCCACCAGGUACUGGGGGCCUGUGGCAGCAAGAUAGGGGGAGAGAGACCCAGAGAUGUGAGAGAGAGUCAGAGACAGAGACAGAGAGAGAGAGAGAGAGACACAGAGAGAGACAGAGAGAGAGCGAGCGAGCGCGCGGCAGCCGCGGGGCGAGGGCCUUUGCUGCUCUGCCGGGGCCUGCUGACUGAAAGGAAUUUGUGUUUUUGCUUUUUUUCCAAAAAGAUCUCCAGCUCCACACAUGUUUCCACUUAAUACCAGAGACCCCCCCCCUUCCCCUCCCCCUUCCCCUCCCCCUUGGGACGCGCUCUAAAUAAUUGCAAUAAAACAAACCUUUCUCUGCAAACCAUUUCCUCCCCGCCCCCUCCCCUCAGCAGCGGCCGUCCUGAGUGGGAGUCCCUGGGACUUCCCAGUGGCCAAGUUGGGGCGCCCAGCCUCUUCGUGGGGACCUUGGGUAAGGCCAGGGAGGCCUGAUGUGGCCGUAGGAGCUGCCCCUGCCCACCUGCCCUGGUGUGGGGGUCCCUAGGCCACACCCUGCUCCCCACCCAGCUACCCUGUGCGCCUGUGCCCUGCUGGGGGCCUGGGCUCUCCGAGGGGCCUGAGGAUGGAGGCCCCACGUCCCCGAGGAGGGCGGCCUCUGGACAGGCCCCUCAUUCCGCGCGGCAGCUCCCAGGCCUGGGGAACGUAGGUGUGUGAGAGCGGCACCCGGGAAGGACGCCUGGCCUCUGGCUCAGCCCUGCUUGGCGGGCUCCCCCGUGGACACCCUGUUGACUUUGCACUUCCCUCCCGGGCCCCGCACCCCCGAACCGACCACCGAUCGACCGGCACCGCUGUUGCCUCGUAAGCCAUAGCGCAUGCGCGCUCUCAGGAUAAACAGGCCCUGCCUGGGA